CUGCCUCCGACUCCCCACUGGACUGCAUGGCGACGGCGUGUGGUGGGGCAGUCAGCUAAGCCAUUUGCCUAAGGGGCUGUCGGGCAUCUGCGUGCUGGGGACCGACAGUGUGGGUGUGUUAGGAGGAUCUGUAUGGAGCACAUUGCUGCCUCUGGCUAGGACAGGGUGGAAAGGGUGGCGUGGCUACAGCCUGACCCAUGGGCACCGUCCUACCCUUUGUUCUGUGCUUCCGAGUGUCAGUCAUGUGCUGGGGUCUGUGGGCCCAUGACUCAGACGGUGAGCUCUGACCUUCCUGAGCCAGGGCUUUGCUGUAGUUGUGCCUGGCUCAGGAGCUCUAGGACAAGGGGACCGCUCCAGGUCUGCAUCUACGGUGUGGCAGGGCCCCUCGGCACUCUUGUGCACUAGUGUCAUCUUUCCCAUUGAAAUGACUGUGAGGACCAGAAUGUGCACAUGCAGAUGGGCAGCUACUUGUCUGCCUUGGCCCUUUAUUACACAACUUGCUGGGGGUGGAGAUGCCACCCCCCGGCAGUCAGAGCCCCUUUAUGAUGUCAUGGGGCUGGUUACAUGACUGCCAAGGGGUGCUGCUGGCCACACUGCACUAGCAAGUUUGCCAGAUGGAGGACAAGCGAUCAUUGAGUAUGGCUCGCUGUGAAGAAAGAAAUUCGAGGGGACAGGAUCAUGGCUUGGAAAGGGUGCCUUUCCCUCCCCAGUUGCAGUCAGAGACCUACCUUCACCCAGCAGAUCCUUCCCCUGCCUGGGACGACCCGGGGUCCACUGGGAGCCCUAACUUGAGGCUGCUGACAGAAGAAAUCGCUUUCCAACCUCUGGCCGAGGAAGCUUCGUUCAGAAGGCCGCACCCUGACGGUGACGUCCCGCCCCAGGGAGAAGAUAAUCUCCUCUCCCUCCCCUUUCCACAGAAACUGUGGAGACUGGUCAGCAGCAACCAGUUUUCGUCCAUCUGGUGGGAUGACAGUGGGGCUUGUAGAGUGAUCAAUCAAAAACUCUUUGAAAAGGAGAUUCUCAAAAGGGACGUCGCACACAAAGUGUUUGCCACAACUUCGAUAAAGAGCUUCUUCCGCCAGCUAAACUUGUAUGGCUUCCGAAAACGGCGUCAAUGCACUUUCAGGACCUUCACCCGCAUUUUCUCCGCAAAAAGGCUGGUCUCCAUCUUGAAUAAGUUAGAGUUCUACUGCCAUCCUUACUUUCAAAGAGACUCCCCUCACCUCCUCGUGAGGAUGAAGAGAAGAGUGGGUGUCAAGUCUGCACCAAGACAUCAGGAGGAGGACAAGCCAGAAGCUGCUGGAUCCUGUCUGGCACCAGCAGACACUGAGCAACAAGAUCACACGUCUCCGAAUGAGAAUGACCAGGUCACACCGCAACACCGGGAACCGGCCGGUCCCAACACCCAAAUCAGGAGUGGCUCUGCUCCACCAGCAACUCCUGUGAUGGUGCCUGAUUCCGCCGUGGCGAGUGACAACAGUCCAGUGACCCAGCCGGCCGGCGAGUGGUCAGAGGGCAGCCAGGCUCACGUCACUCCGGUGGCCGCUGUCCCUGGGCCUGCAGCGCUGCCCUUCCUCUAUGUCCCUGGAUCUCCCACUCAGAUGAAUUCUUACGGGCCUGUGGUGGCCCUUCCCACAGCGUCCCGUAGUACCCUUGCCAUGGACACCACAGGACUUCCUGCACCUGGCAUGCUGCCCUUUUGCCAUCUCUGGGUACCGGUGACCCUAGUGGCUGCUGGGGCUGCACAGCCUGCUGCCUCCAUGGUCAUGUUCCCCCAUCUCCCAGCUCUGCACCACCAUUGCCCCCACAGCCACCGCACGUCACAGUACAUGCCAGCUAGCGAUGGGCCCCAGGCGUACCCAGACUACGCAGACCAGAGCACAUAGAGGGCAGCAUUUGGGCAGAAUAUGUGCUGGUCAAUAAAUGUGUCAGAAAAUGAGUAAUUUUCUGACUGCACAAAAAAGUC